GAGUGGCUUCACCGCCGGUCCCUUGCAGCGCUGCCUUUCGAUCUCUCCACAUCUCGGUGGCGCGGGAUCUCAAGAUGCGCCUCCACCUGCUCCUGCUGCUCGCGCUGUGCGGUGCAGGCACCACCGCCGCGGAGCUCAGUUACAGCUUGCGUGGCAACUGGAGCAUCUGCAAUGGGAACGGCUCGCUGGAGCUGCCCGGGGCGGUCCCUGGCUGCGUGCACAGCGCCUUGUUCCAGCAGGGCCUGAUCCAGUUGAAGAAGCAUCUAUCUGUAGGGAAUCCAGAAGGAGCGUUCAUGAAGGUAUUACAAGCCCGGAAGAAGCACACGAGCACUGAGCUGACUACUGAGCUGGAGGCGGCCUCAGACAGCAAUGGCAUCAACUUGUCAGGCUUUGGGAGUGAGCAGCUAGACAUCAAUGACGCACUAAAUUACGUCUUGCCUUAUUUCUCAUAGAAAAAUCUAUAAGAUGUAGAAUCAAUGUUGUUACUGUUAGGGACGAGCUGCCCCAGGAACCGCCCCCGCAGUGCAGCUGACCCUUACCCCGAAUACUCUGCAGCUGCAUUCCUGAACCCUUAUCUAGGUGCCACAGCAAGGUUGCCGACUUGCUACACUAAGCAAACCCUGCUUACAGCCCUCCAGGUGGCACAGGGAAGGUCAUGAGAAAUGUGGAUAAAUCUAAGUUAUACCCUCUUGUAAAUUCCUCCGGUCAUGAGACGAUAUGUGGUAAAGUUAACUGAAAAGACCAAGAAGCAGCUUCUCCACUCCUUCUGGGAUCUCUAUCUGGUUCGGCCUUCCUGCCCCCACUCCUGCCUCCACCAUGUCCAUCAGGGUGACCCAGAAGUCCUACAAGGUGUCCACCUCUGGGCCCCGGGCCUUCAGCAGCCACUCCUACACAAGUGGGCCCAGUGUCCAGAUAAGCUCCUCAGGCUUCUCCCUAGUGGGCAGCAGCAGCUUCCAAGGUUGUCUGGGCGGAGGCUAUGGUGAGGGCAGCAGCGUGGGUGGCAUCACCACCAUCACAGUCAACCAGAGCCUGCUGAGCCCCCUUAACCUGGAGGUGGACCCCAACAUCCAGGCUGUGCGCACCCAGGAGAAGCAGCAGAUCAAGACCCUCAACAACAAGUUUGCCUCCUUCAUAGACAAGGUAUGGUUCCUGGAGCAGUAGAACAAGAUGCUGGAGACUAAGUGGAGCCUCCUGCAGCAGCAGAAGAUGGCUCAGAGCAACAUGGACAACAUGUUCCAGAGCUACAUCAACAACCUUAGGCAGCAGCUGAAGACUCUGGGCCAGGAGAAGCUGAAGCUGGAGGCGGAGCUUGGCAACAUGCCCGGGCUGGUGGAGGACUUCAAGAACAAGUAUGAGGAUGAGAUCAAUAAGUGUACAGAGGUGGAGAAUGAAUUUGUCCUCAUCAAGAGGAUGUGGAUGAAGGUUACAUGAACAAGGUAGAGCUGGAGUCUCACCUGGAAGGGCUGACUGACGAGAUCAAUUUCCUCAAGCAGCUGUAUGAAGAGGAGAUCCAGGAGCUGCAGUCCCAGAUCUCGGACACAUCUGUGGUGCUGCCCAUGGACAACAGCCGCUCCCUGGGCAUGAACAGCAUCAUCGCUGAGGUCAAGGCACCAUACGAGGAGAUCGCCAACUGCAGCCAGGCCAAGGCUGAGAGCAUGUACCAGAUCAAGGAUGAGGAGCUGCAGAUGCUGGCUGGGAAGCACGAGGAUGACCUGCAGUGUACAAAGACUGAGAUUUCUGAGAUGAACCGGAACAUCAGCCAGCUCCAGGCUGAGACUGAGGGCCUCAAAGGCCAGAGGGCUUCCCUGGAGGGCACCAUCACAGAUGUCUGCAGCACAGGGGGCUGGCUGUUAAGGAUGCCAACGCCAAGCUGUCCAAGCUGGAGGCCGCCCUGCAGCAGGCCAAGCAGGACAUGGCAUGGCAACUGCUUGAGUACCAGGAACUGAUGAACAUCAAGCUGGCCCUGGACAUCGAGAUAGCCACCUACAGGAAGCUGCUGGAGGGCGAGGAGAGCCAGCUGGACUCUGGGAUGCAGAACAUGAGUAUCCAUACAAAGACCACCAGUGGUUAUGCAGGUGAUCUGAGCUCGGCCUGUGGGGGCCUCCCAAGCCCCAGCUUUGGCUCUGGUGUGGGCUCCAGCUCCUUCAGCCGCACCAGCACCACCAGGGCAGUGGUUGUGAAGAAGAUCGAGACCCAUGAUGGGAGGCUGGUGUCCUAGUCCUCUGACGUCCUGCCCAAGUGAACAGCUGCGGCAGCCCCUCCCAGCCUGCCCCUCCUGCGACUCUCCCAGAGAGCAGAAGGGAGCACAGGGAACGUGAGACCCACCUGAGGCCCAGCCCUAGCCCUCAACCCACCCACAGGGUAGUUUACUACCUGGGGACCCCCCAUGCCUAUGCCUUCAGCUACAAAACAAUUCAAUUGCUUUUUUUUUUUGGUCCAAAAUAAAACCUCUGCUAGCUCUGCCAACAGCUAACCUUAUAGUUACCUGUUUUUUUCAAAUGUGAAAGAUGGGUAUUCCGAAAAACCAUACAAAGAGUCCCUCUCUUCAAUCUGCAUCCAAAAACUCAUGAAAUUAGAAACUGUCCAACCACAGGAAAACAGCCUGGCUAAGAUUCAAAGUGUAGGCAAAAGCCUGCAGAGAGUGAACAGAAUCCUCAUGGGCCCAAGGAGCAUCCAGAAAAGUCACUUCAAAGAGGUGGGAAAGCAGAGCAACAGGAAGGAACAGGGUGCCUGGGCAUUUGUGGAGAAUGCUGCCAAAGAAAAAAGGCUCAGGAGUCCAGCCCCAAGGGAGCUGGAACAGCCUCACAUAGAGCAGGGGCAUGAGAAGUUAGCAGGAAACGCCAUCUAUACCAAGCCUUCGUUCAACCAAGAGCAUAAGGCAGCAGUCUUCUCUUUGCUGAAACCCUUCUCCAUGGGCGUGCCUUCUAUCUCCACCCCUGCAAAAGCCCUACCUGUGGUCAGAAACAGAUUGAAAGACUUACCCAUUUUGGUUUUAGAAAAUGCAAAGUUGAGUUAAAACCAAUCGUACAUUCCAGAAAAGUUCUCUCAGUAGACUUUGCUUGCAAAGAGGCCUCCAUUCUCUGCAGUGAAAAGCCUCAUAAAUGCCCCUUCACAAGGGGCUUUUUCAUCUUUAGGAGACCUGAGUCUUCAGGAAAAUCCUUUUCCGGAAGUAUUUCUCCAUCAGAAUGUUUUAAAAGCACCACUGCAAGAAAUGCCUUUGAACAAAACAUUUUUAUGGAAAACACUACUAUGCCAGAAGGCACCAUCUCUGAAAACACAACCUACAACCAUCCUCCUGAGGGAGAUUCUGCUGAGACUGCGUUCAACUUAGAGAAGACUGUGAAACACAAUGGGAAUACAACAACAUGGGCACUGGCCUGUCUCCCGAGCCCAAAAGCUUCAAUUACCCAUUGCUCUCGUCCCCAGGUGAUCAGUUUGAAAUUCAGCUAAACCAGCAGCUACGGCCCCUCAUCCCCAAUAAUGAUGUGAGAAGACUCAUUUCUCAUGUUAUCUGGACCUUGAAGAUGGAGUGCUCUGAGACCCAUGUGCAAUUGGCCUAUACCAAGCUCAUCUCCAGGACAGGCCUCCUGAUUCAUCAGUGAGCAGCAAGAAGUAAAGAUGUCCAAGGCAGAAUGGGAUACAGACCAAUGGAAAACUGAGAACUAUAUCAAUGAGAGCACGGAAGCCCAGAGCAAACAGAAAGAGCAGAAGUCAAGUGAGGAUUCUUACUACAGAUUUAAUGACCUUAACUACAGAUGGGUCUCUUUGGAUAACUGGACCUAUAGCAAAGAAUUUAAAAUCCCCUUUGAAAUUAGCAAAUGGCAAAAAGUAAAUUUGAUUCUUGAGGGAGUGGAUACGGUUUCAAAAAUCCUGUUCAAUGAAGUCACUAUUGGGGAAACAGACAAUAUGUUCAAUAGAUAUAGCUUUGAUAUUACCAACGUGGUCAGGGACGUGAACUCCAUUGAGCUGCGUUUCCAGUCAGCGGUGUUGUAUGCAGCACAGCAGAGCAAAGCUCACACUCGCUACCAGGUUCCCCCAGACUGCCCUCCACUUGUGCAGAAGGGUGAAUGCCAUGUCAACUUUGUUCGGAAGGAGCAAUGUUCCUUUAGUUGGGACUGGGGGCCUUCCUUUCCUACCCAGGGAAUCUGGAAAGAUGUUAGAAUUGAAGCCUAUAAUAUUUGUCACCUGAACUACUUCACAUUUUCCCCAAUAUAUGAUAAGAGUGCCCAGGAGUGGAAUCUGGAAAUAGAGUCUACAUUUGAUGUUGUCAGCUCAAAGCCAGUUGGUGGUCAAGUGAUCGUAGCCAUCCCUAAGUUGCAAACACAACAGACAUACAGCAUUGAACUUCAACCUGGGAAAAGGAUUGUUGAGCUAUUUGUGAACAUUAGCAAGAAUAUUACUGUAGAAACUUGGUGGCCUCAUGGACAUGGAAACCAGACUGGGUACAACAUGACUGUUCUUUUUGAACUGGAUGGAGGCUUAAAUAUUGAAAAAUCAGCUAAGGUUUAUUUUAGGACAGUGGAACUUAUAGAAGAGCCUAUAAAAGGGUCUCCUGGUUUGAGUUUCUAUUUCAAAAUUAAUGGAUUUCCCAUAUUUCUAAAAGGCUCAAACUGGAUCCCAGCAGAUUCAUUCCAGGACCGAGUAACCUCUGAGUUGUUACGGCUCCUUUUACAGUCUGUUGUGGAUGCUAAUAUGAAUACUCUUCGGGUUUGGGGAGGAGGAAUUUAUGAGCAGGAUGAAUUCUAUGAACUCUGUGAUGAACUAGGAAUAAUGGUAUGGCAGGAUUUUAUGUUUGCCUGUGCCCUUUAUCCAACUGAUCAGGGCUUCCUGGAUUCAGUGACAGCAGAAGUUGCCUACCAGAUCAAGAGACUGAAAUCUCAUCCUUCUAUCAUCAUAUGGAGUGGCAAUAAUGAAAAUGAGGAGGCGCUGAUGAUGAAUUGGUAUCAUAUCAGUUUCACUGACCGGCCAAUCUACAUCAAGGACUAUGUGACACUCUAUGUGAAAAACAUCAGAGAGCUCGUACUGGCAGGAGACAAGAGUCGUCCUUUUAUUACGUCCAGUCCUACAAAUGGGGCUGAAACUGUUGCAGAAGCCUGGGUCUCUCAAAACCCUAAUAGCAAUUAUUUUGGUGAUGUACAUUUUUAUGACUAUAUCAGUGAUUGCUGGAACUGGAAAGUUUUCCCAAAAGCUCGAUUUGCAUCUGAAUAUGGAUAUCAGUCCUGGCCGUCCUUCAGUACAUUAGAAAAGGUCUCGUCUACAGAGGACUGGUCUUUCAAUAGCAAGUUUUCACUUCAUCGACAACAUCACGAAGGUGGUAACAAACAAAUGCUUUAUCAGGCUGGACUUCAUUUCAAACUCCCCCAAAGCACAGAUCCAUUACGCACAUUUAAAGAUACCAUCUACCUUACUCAGGUGAUGCAGGCCCAGUGUGUCAAAACAGAAACUGAAUUCUACCGCCGUAGUCGCAGCGAGAUAGUGGAUCAGCAAGGGCACACGAUGGGGGCACUUUAUUGGCAGUUGAAUGACAUCUGGCAAGCUCCUUCCUGGGCUUCUCUUGAGUACGGAGGAAAGUGGAAAAUGCUUCAUUACUUUGCUCAGAAUUUCUUUGCUCCACUGUUGCCAGUAGGCUUUGAGAAUGAAAACACGUUCUAUAUCUAUGGUGUGUCAGAUCUUCACUCGGAUUAUUCGAUGACACUCAGUGUGAGAGUCCAUACAUGGAGCUCCCUGGAGCCCGUGUGCUCUCGUGUGACUGAACGUUUUGUGAUGAAAGGAGGAGAGGCUGUCUGCCUUUAUGAGGAGCCAGUGUCUGAAUUGCUGAGGAGAUGUGGGAAUUGCACACGGGAAAGCUGUGUGGUUUCCUUUUACCUUUCAGCUGACCAUGAACUCCUGAGCCCGACCAACUACCACUUCUUGUCCUCACCGAAGGAGGCCGUGGGGCUCUGCAAGGCGCAGAUCACUGCCAUCAUCUCUCAGCAAGGUGACAUAUUUGUUUUUGACCUGGAGACCUCAGCUGUCGCUCCCUUUGUUUGGUUGGAUGUAGGAAGCAUCCCAGGGAGAUUUAGUGACAAUGGUUUCCUCAUGACUGAGAAGACACGAACUAUAUUAUUUUACCCUUGGGAGCCCACCAGCAAGAAUGAGUUGGAGCAAUCUUUUCAUGUGACCUCCUUAACAGAUAUUUACUGAAGGAAUCUAGGUUGUAUUUUCAGUGGACAAUGGGAAUAAAGCAUUUCUAAAGCACCGACUGGAGAGGAAGGCAACAGAGACAAGGAGAGAAGCCGAGAGACAUGUCUGCGUGCUGCCACGCAUUUGAGCGAUUGCUCUGUGAAGAGUUGUACACUGAACACUUUCAGGGGAGGCUGUUUACCCAGGCAAUGUCCUCAAACAAGCCUGUGCCGGGGUGUCCUGGAAUCUGUGCCAGGACUGUGUUUUUAGCCCUUCACCUCUCAGCUUUAGCAGGACAUGAACCAGUUAUAACAAGAUGGCCCUGCAGCUGGUUACAAGAAUGUGACAUGGCAGGAUCUAUGGAACCAAAUGGAAGGUUUUGAGGUGAUGUAGGUCUUUCACAGCUAGCUUUGGGGAAUACGGAAUACUCAAAUAAAGUGCUUUGUUAUUAUUUCAGAGGGAAUGGCGAUUGAAAUGUUACAACAGAGAUUUCUUGGUGGUAGCUAUUUGGGUAAAGGUAUAUGGGUAUUUUUCUGUACAUGUGAAAUUAUAUAAAAAUAAAAGUUAUAUAAAUUACAUUGACAACUUGAUAUUUCAUCUGUGGCUUAUUUAACCGUUCUAUAAAUAUUCAAUUUUGCCCAAUACUGUGCUGGACCCUAAUUUCCAUUUAGUUCUCGUUAUUAUUCUGCUUGGUAAACUGGGAGAGUUUGAAGAAUCUAAACUAAGACAUGUGAAAGGUUUUCUCUGGAAACAGUCAUGUAAUUGGUUAUAGAAUGGACCAGCAAAGAGUGUUUGGCUUUAAAAUUAAGAUAUUAUUAGUGGUUUUGGUUUUAAAAAUGAGAAGCAUUAUGUUCAGUGACUCUAAAAGUAACUACAGACAAUCCAGUCUUCUUCAGUAUCUAAGAGUAUCCUCAUUUUAUAUGUACACACACACACACACACACACACACACACACACACACACACACACAAAGCCUUAUCAAGGGGAUAAGGGGACUUAGGGCUGGGACUCCGUAGAGUCUUACUUGGUAAAUAUUAUGUCAUGUUCUUAUGACUAUUGUAAAUCCUGUUUUAGCAAAGCAUUGCUGCGAGGCAGGGAGGACUGCUCUUCUUGACACCUGUGCAUGUUCUGCCAGGGGCCCUGAGAAGGGGCUUUCAAGCUGAUGAGCCAGAGUUUACUUUGUAGUUUGCCCUUACUAGUUCUGUAACCUUAAUCAAGUUACUUAACUUCCUGUGCUCAGUUUUCUUGUGGCUAAAUGGGAGUGGUAACACCCACCUUGUAAGUUUGUUUUGAAGAAUAAAUAAAAU